CUGCCGCUCACCCUAUUCCAGGGACACAGUCUGCUUGGCUCUUCUGGACUGAGCCAUCCUCAUCACCGAGAUCCUCCCUGAAUUCAGCCCACGACAGCCACCCCGGCCGUUUUCCUUGUUCUGUGUGGGGAGGGAGGCAGCGCGGUGGUUAUCAACCUCACCCUGCAGAGGAGGCACCUGAGGCCCAGAGACGAGGAGGGAUGGGUCUAACCCAGAACCACAGAUGGCUCUGAGCCGGGGGCCUGUCCACCCUCCCAGGCCGACGUCAGUGGCCGCAGGACUGCCUGGGCCCUGCUAGGCCUGCUCACCUCUGAGGCCUCUGGGGUGAGAGGUUCAGUCCUGGAAACACUUCAGUUCUAGGGGGCUGGGGGCAGCAGCAAGUUGGAGUUUUGGGGUACCCUGCUUCACAGGGCCCUUGGCAAGGAGGGCAGGUGGGGUCUAAGGACAAGCAGUCCUUACUUUGGGAGUCAACCCCGGCGUGGUGGCUGCUGCAGGUUGCACACUGGGCCACAGAGGAUCCAGCAAGGAUGAAGAAAUGGAGCAGCACAGACUUGGGGGCAGCUGCGGACCCACUCCAAAAGGACACCUGCCCAGACCCCCUGGAUGGAGACCCUAACUCCAGGCCACCUCCAGCCAAGCCCCAGCUCUCCACGGCCAAGAGCCGCACCCGGCUCUUUGGGAAGGGUGACUCGGAGGAGGCUUUCCCGGUGGAUUGCCCUCACGAGGAAGGUGAGCUGGACUCCUGCCCGACCAUCACAGUCAGCCCUGUUAUCACCAUCCAGAGGCCAGGAGACGGCCCCACCGGUGCCAGGCUGCUGUCCCAGGACUCUGUCGCCGCCAGCACCGAGAAGACCCUCAGGCUCUAUGAUCGCAGGAGUAUCUUUGAAGCCGUUGCUCAGAAUAACUGCCAGGAUCUGGAGAGCCUGCUGCUCUUCCUGCAGAAGAGCAAGAAGCACCUCACAGACAACGAGUUCAAAGACCCUGAGACAGGGAAGACCUGUCUGCUGAAAGCCAUGCUCAACCUGCACGACGGACAGAACACCACCAUCCCCCUGCUCCUGGAGAUCGCGCGGCAAACGGACAGCCUGAAGGAGCUUGUCAACGCCAGCUACACGGACAGCUACUACAAGGGCCAGACAGCACUGCACAUCGCCAUCGAGAGACGCAACAUGGCCCUGGUGACCCUCCUGGUGGAGAACGGAGCAGACGUCCAGGCUGCGGCCCAUGGGGACUUCUUUAAGAAAACCAAAGGGCGGCCUGGAUUCUACUUCGGUGAACUGCCCCUGUCCCUGGCCGCGUGCACCAACCAGCUGGGCAUCGUGAAGUUCCUGCUGCAGAACUCCUGGCAGACGGCCGACAUCAGCGCCAGGGACUCGGUGGGCAACACGGUGCUGCACGCCCUGGUGGAGGUGGCCGACAACACGGCCGACAACACGAAGUUUGUGACGAGCAUGUACAAUGAGAUUCUGAUGCUGGGGGCCAAACUGCACCCGACGCUGAAGCUGGAGGAGCUCACCAACAAGAAGGGAAUGACGCCGCUGGCUCUGGCAGCUGGGACCGGGAAGAUCGGGGUCUUGGCCUAUAUUCUCCAGCGGGAGAUCCAGGAGCCCGAGUGCAGGCACCUGUCCAGGAAGUUCACCGAGUGGGCCUACGGGCCCGUGCACUCCUCGCUGUACGACCUGUCCUGCAUCGACACCUGCGAGAAGAACUCGGUGCUGGAGGUGAUCGCCUACAGCAGCAGCGAGACCCCUAAUCGCCACGACAUGCUCUUGGUGGAGCCGCUGAACCGACUCCUGCAGGACAAGUGGGACAGAUUCGUCAAGCGCAUCUUCUACUUCAACUUCCUGGUCUACUGCCUGUACAUGAUCAUCUUCACCAUGGCUGCCUACUACAGGCCCGUGGAUGGCUUGCCUCCCUUUAAGAUGGAAAAAACUGGAGACUAUUUCCGAGUUACUGGAGAGAUCCUGUCUGUGUUAGGAGGAGUCUACUUCUUUUUCCGAGGGAUUCAGUAUUUCCUGCAGAGGCGGCCGUCGAUGAAGACCCUGUUUGUGGACAGCUACAGUGAGAUGCUUUUCUUUCUGCAGUCACUGUUCAUGCUGGCCACCGUGGUGCUGUACUUCAGCCACCUCAAGGAGUAUGUGGCUUCCAUGGUAUUCUCCCUGGCCUUGGGCUGGACCAACAUGCUCUACUACACCCGCGGUUUCCAGCAGAUGGGCAUCUAUGCCGUCAUGAUAGAGAAGAUGAUCCUGAGAGACCUGUGCCGUUUCAUGUUUGUCUACAUCGUCUUCUUGUUCGGGUUUUCCACAGCGGUGGUGACGCUGAUUGAAGACGGGAAGAAUGACUCCCUGCCGUCUGAGUCCACGUCGCACAGGUGGCGGGGGCCUGCCUGCAGGCCCCCCGAUAGCUCCUACAACAGCCUGUACUCCACCUGCCUGGAGCUGUUCAAGUUCACCAUCGGCAUGGGCGACCUGGAGUUCACUGAGAACUAUGACUUCAAGGCUGUCUUCAUCAUCCUGCUGCUGGCCUAUGUAAUUCUCACCUACAUCCUCCUGCUCAACAUGCUCAUCGCCCUCAUGGGUGAGACUGUCAACAAGAUCGCACAGGAGAGCAAGAACAUCUGGAAGCUGCAGAGAGCCAUCACCAUCCUGGACACGGAGAAGAGCUUCCUUAAGUGCAUGAGGAAGGCCUUCCGCUCAGGCAAGCUGCUGCAGGUGGGGUACACACCUGAUGGCAAGGACGACUACCGGUGGUGCUUCAGGGUGGACGAGGUGAACUGGACCACCUGGAACACCAACGUGGGCAUCAUCAACGAAGACCCGGGCAACUGUGAGGGCGUCAAGCGCACCCUGAGCUUCUCCCUGCGGUCAAGCAGAGUUUCAGGCAGACACUGGAAGAACUUUGCCCUGGUCCCCCUUUUAAGAGAGGCAAGUGCUCGAGAUAGGCAGUCUGCUCAGCCCGAGGAAGUUUAUCUGCGACAGUUUUCAGGGUCUCUGAAGCCAGAGGACGCUGAGGUCUUCAAGAGUCCUGCCGCUUCCGGGGAGAAGUGAGGACGUCACGCAGACAGCACUGUCAACACUGGGCCUUAGGAGACCCCGUUGCCACGGGGGGCUGCUGAGGGAACACCAGUGCUCUGUCAGCAGCCUGGCCUGGUCUGUGCCUGCCCAGCAUGUUCCCAAAUCUGUGCUGGACAAGCUGUGGGAAGCGUUCUUGGAAGCAUGGGGAGUGAUGUACAUCCAACCGUCACUGUCCCCAAGUGAAUCUCCUAACAGACUUUCAGGUUUUUACUCACUUUACUAAACAGUUUGGAUGGUCAGUCUCUACUGGGACAUGUUAGGCCCUUGUUUUCUUUGAUUUUAUUCUUUUUUUUGAGACAGAAUUUCACUCUUCUCACCCAGGCUGGAAUGCAGUGGCACAAUUUUGGCUCCCUGCAACCUCCGCCUCCUGGAUUCCAGCAAUUCUCCUGCCUCGGCUUCCCAAGUAGCUGGGAUUACAGGCACGUGCCACCAUGUCUGGCUAAUUUUUUGUAUUUUUUUAAUAGAUAUGGGGUUUCGCCAUGUUGGCCAGGCUGGUCUCGAACUCCUGACCUCAGGUGAUCCGCCCACCUCGGCCUCCCAAAGUGCUGGGAUUACAGGUGUGAGCCUCCACACCUGGCUGUUUUCUUUGAUUUUAUUCUUUUUUUUUUUUUCUGUGAGACAGAGUUUCACUCUUGUUGCCCAGGCUGGAGUGCAGUGGUGUGAUCUUGGCUCACUGCAACUUCUGCCUCCCGGGUUCAAGCGAUUCUUCUGCUUCAGUCUCCCAAGUAGCUUGGAUUACAGGUGAGCACUACCACGCCCGGCUAAUUUUUGUAUUUUUAAUAGAGACGGGGUUUCACCAUGUUGGCCAGGCUGGUCUCGAACUCUUGACCUCAGGUGAUCUGCCCGCCUUGGCCUCCCAAAGUGCUGGGAUUACAGGUGUGAGCCGCUGCGCUCGGCCUUCUUUGAUUUUAUAUUAUUAGGAGCAAAAGUAAAUGAAGCCCAGGAAAACACCUUUGGGAACAAACUCUUCCUUUGAUGGAAAAUGCAGAGGCCCUUCCUCUCUGUGCCGUGCUUGCUCCUCUUACCUGCCCGGGUGGUUUGGGGGUGUUGGUGUUUCCUCCCUGGAGAAGAUGGGGGAGGCUGUCCCACUCCCAGCUCUGGCAGAAUCAAGCUGUUGCAGCAGUGCCUUCUUCAUCCUUCCUUACGAUCAAUCACAGUCUCCAGAAGAUCAGCUCAAUUGCUGUGCAGGUUAAAACUACAGAACCACAUCCCAAAGGUACCUGGUAAGAAUGUUUGAAAGAUCUUCCAUUUCUAGGAACCCCAGUCCUGCUUCUCCGCAAUGGCACAUGCUUCCACUCCAUCCAUACUGGCAUCCUCAAAUAAACAGAUAUGUAUACAUAUA